CACUCACUCACACACUCACUCACUCACACACCUCCCCCAGCUCACCGCCUCCCCACUCCAGCAUGGCCGCCUCCACCAUGUCCAUCUGCUCCAGCGCCUGCACUGACUCUUGGCGGGUAGUCGACUGCCCAGAGAGCUGCUGCGAGCCCUGCUGCUGUGCCCCAGCCCCCAGCUUGACCCUGGUCUGCACCCCAGUGAGCUGUGUGUCCAGCCCCUGCUGCCAGACGGCCUGUGAGCCCAGCGCCUGCCAAUCAGGCUACACCAGCUCCUGCACAACCCCAUGCUACCAGCAGUCUAGCUGCCAGCCGGAUUGCUGCACCUCCUCCCCCUGCCAGCAGGCCUGCUGUGUGCCUGUCUGCUGUGUGCCCGUCUGCUGCGUGCCCGUCUGUAACAAGCCUGUGUGCUUCGUGCCUACCUGCUCCGAGUCUUCCCCUUCAUGCUGCCAGCAGUCUAGCUGCCAGCCAACUUGCUGCACCUCCUCCCCAUGCCAGCAGGCCUGCUGUGUGCCUGUCUGCUCUAAGUCCGUCUGCUAUGUGCCUGUGUGCUCUGGGGCUUCCACUUCAUGCUGCCAGCAGUCUAGCUGCCAGCCUGCUUGCUGCACCGCCUCCUGCUGCAGACCCUCCUCCUCCGUGUCCCUCCUCUGCCACCCUGUGUGCAAGUCCACCUGCUGCGUGCCCGUCCCCUCCUGCGGUGCCUCUGCCUCCUCCUGCCAGCCCAGCUGCUGCCGCACGGCCUCCUGUGUUUCCCUCCUCUGCCGCCCCGUGUGCUCCCGCCCUGCCUGCUACAGCCUCUGCUCUGGCCAGAAGUCCAGCUGCUGACAGCCCUGGAUGUGAUCCGGAGUCCCUUCCCACCAGGGGCUGACCUCCCAGCUGCCCCAGCAAGCUCUGCCCUCUCUGGCUUUGACACCCUCAGAAGGUGGGGCAGGCUCUUUGUCUUGGGGACCAGGAUGCUCCCCCAGUCCUUCCCAGAUGAUGGCUGCCUGUGGGACCCCAGCUACUCCCCCAGACCCAAGUUCUGCAGAACUAACCCCCAGCAGGCCUGGUUCCACCCUGGGCAGCACCCCCUCUAGUUCUAAUAAAGCCGCCUCUGUCUCACACCAA